CCAAGCCUGAGAAUCAGGAGAAGCCUCACAGUGACACCCCCAACUGAGGAAACUCACAGAGCUGGGACAUACUCUACUUCUUCAGAAAAAAGUAUACUGACUAGAGUGGAGUCCCCCUGGGGAGUCAGAAAGCCUGUGAAAGAUCUCACUUGUUCAAAAGUCCAAGUGUGAAUUACUGUCUCACAGAUAAACCAAAGUAUUUUGAAAAACAAAGGGGAGAAAAGAAAUUACUCCCCAGAACUCUCAGGCAUCUAGAGGACACCCAAGAACGUGGGAGUCAGCUGCUUCUUGUGUGCAGCCAUGAAGUCUGUGCACUCCAGUCCCCAGAACACGAGUCAUACCAUCAUGACGUUUUACCCAACCAUGGAAGAAUUUGCAGAUUUCAACACAUAUGUUGCUUACAUGGAGUCCCAAGGCGCACAUCAAGCUGGCCUUGCCAAGGUAAUUCCACCCAAGGAAUGGAAAGCCAGACAGAUGUAUGAUGAUAUCGAAGACAUCUUAAUAGCCACUCCCCUCCAGCAGGUGACCUCUGGGCAGGGAGGUGUGUUUACUCAAUACCAUAAAAAGAAGAAAGCCAUGAGGGUGGGGCAGUAUCGCCGCUUGGCAAACAGUAAAAAAUAUCAGACUCCGCCACACCAGAAUUUUGCAGAUUUGGAGCAACGAUACUGGAAGAGCCACCCCGGUAAUCCACCAAUUUAUGGUGCUGAUAUCAGCGGCUCCUUAUUUGAAGAAAGCACUAAACAAUGGAACCUAGGACACCUGGGAACAAUUCUGGACCUGUUGGAGCAGGAAUGUGGGGUUGUCAUCGAGGGUGUCAACACACCCUACCUGUACUUUGGCAUGUGGAAGACCACGUUUGCCUGGCACACAGAGGACAUGGACCUUUACAGCAUCAACUACCUGCACUUUGGGGAGCCCAAAACUUGGUACGUGGUGCCCCCAGAACAUGGUCAGCACCUGGAACGCCUGGCCAGGGAGCUCUUCCCAGACAUUUCUCGGGGCUGUGAGGCCUUCCUGCGGCACAAAGUGGCCCUCAUCUCGCCUACAGUUCUCAAGGAAAAUGGGAUUCCCUUCAAUUGCAUGACUCAGGAGGCUGGGGAGUUCAUGGUGACCUUUCCCUAUGGCUACCAUGCUGGCUUCAAUCACGGCUUCAACUGCGCAGAAGCCAUUAAUUUUGCCACUCCACGAUGGAUUGAUUAUGGCAAAAUGGCCUCUCAGUGUAGCUGUGGGGAGUCGACAGUGACCUUUUCCAUGGACCCCUUUGUGCGCAUUGUGCAACCCGAGAGUUAUGAGCUCUGGAAACACAGGCAAGACUUGGCCAUUGUGGAACACACAGAGCCCAGGGUUGCAGAAAGCCAAGAGCUGAGCAACUGGAGAGAUGAUAUAGUACUUAGAAGAGCUGCUCUGGGCCUGAGGCUUCUCCCAAACCUCACAGCCCAGUGUCCCACACAGCCUGUGUCCUCAGGGCACUGUUACAACCCAAAAGGCUGUGGCACUGAUGCUGUGCCUGGAUCCGCAUUCCAAAGCUCUGCAUAUCAUACCCAGACCCAGUCACUUACCCUGGGGAUGUCAGCCAGGGUUCUUCUCCCUUCCACUGGAAGCUGGGGUUCUGGUCGUGGUCGUGGUCGUGGUCAAGGUCAAGGUCGAGGUUGCAGUCGUGGUCGUGGUCAUGGUUGUUGUACUCGAGAACUGGGGACUGAGGAGCCAACUGUUCAGCCUGCAUCCAAGAGGCGCCUUUUAAUGGGUACAAGGAGUAGAGCUCAAGGCCACAGGCCUCAGCUCCCGCUUGCCAAUGAUUUGAUGACAAAUCUGUCCCUUUGAGUGGUGGCCUUCAGCAUCUUGCCAAGGCUUCUGGCUGCUGCUGUGUCCCUGAUCUUCAACUCCUGGGGCCCCCACUGGAUCGUGAUGAAACCAUGCACCCUGGCCUGUGCCUGCUAUCCCUCAACAGCACUACUAGUAAUCUCCCUGAUGUUGUCUGCAUGACUCCUCCCAAUGUCAUUGUGCCUUUGAUUAAGUUUUCCAGGGACACUGGUGGGGACUGGAACUGAUUAAGUUCACCAGGGACACUUGCCUGGUGAACAUGGGCAAGGCUGUAGCAAUGGACCACUUUUACGGCUCUAGGGUUCUGACUCCAACUAAGUUUUCCAGAAUCUCCUGGGCUCCUGACUCAUCUGCUGGGUCUAAAGACACUGAGUUUAGGGAUAUUUUCCUCCAAUACAUGAUCAAUCCUCUGGAUCCACGGCUAUGGAAUAUGGUGACAAAUGUCAGUGUCUCUCUUAUUCCAACCCCAGGAUCAGAGAAGAUUCUUUACCUGCAGUAACUGACACAUUUCCAAGGCC